GAGAGCGCGCGGCGGGGCGUCCCGGAACAGUCUGCGCCAGACGGGCGGCGGCGUGAGGGCUCCGGGUCGCUGGCGGCGUGGACACCUGAGUCCCGGGGUAGGGGUCUCCCGCGAGUGAUGCCUCCCGUUAUGUUACGGUACAGCAGGAAGGCCUUCAGCAGAUGUGGCCCUGGAUCUUGGAUUUCCCAACCUCCCAAACCACAAGCCAAAUAAGUUUGUUCCUUGUACAGCAGCACAAAACAGAUGAAGACAAUGGCUGUGGCAAUAAUGUAGGCACGUGCUAAAAUGGUCCUGAACUUGGGUGUGGGACCAGAAGGGAAGUGGAUACAACUGACGUCGUAAAGGAAGAGUCUGCAGGGCUCGGCAGCUGGCUGCUUGAGUGAGCUGUUGCCGCAGAAUGGGCUGCUGGCUCCUGCCCUGCUUCCUGUGAUCGAGCCGGCCCUGAGGACUCUGUGGAGAUGCCUGUAACCCACCGGAAAUCAGACGCAUCUGACAUGAACUCAGACACGUCCCCCAGCUGCAGGCUCCGAGCCUUCAGCAGAGGCGGCAGCCUGGAGAGUCGAAGCAGCAGCUCUCGCUCCAGAAGCUUCACUUUGGAUGAUGAGAGCCUGAAGUACCUCACCCAUGAGGAAAAGGAUGUGCUCCUGUUUUUUGAAGAGACGAUUGACUCCCUAGACGAGGACUUUGAGGAGCCAGUGCUGUGCGAUGGAGGAGUGUGCUGCCUCUGCUCCCCGUCUCUGGAGGAGAGCACCUCCAGUCCCUCCGAGCCUGAAGAUGUCAUCGACUUAGUGCAGCCAGCACCUGGCGCCGGGGAAGCCGAGGGCCUUCCAGAGGGGACCCAGGCAGCAGGGCCUGCACCUGCUGGGAAGGAGCACAGGAAACAAGAUGCUGAGACUCCUCCACCUCCAGACCCCCCGGCUCCCGAGACCCUUCUUGCGCCACCACCCCUGCCUAGCACCCCCGAUCCCCCCAGGAGGGAGCUGCGCGCCCCCUCCCCGCCGGUGGAGCACCCCAGACUCCUGCGCUCUGUUCCCACGCCCCUCGUUAUGGCGCAGAAGAUUUCCGAGAGGAUGGCGGGGAACGAAGCCCUCUCGCCCACCUCCCCGUUCAGGGAGGGCCGGCCCGGGGAGUGGAGGACACCUGCCGCCCGGGGGCCCCGCAGUGGAGACCCUGGCCCGGGGCCCAGCCACCCGGCGCAGCCCAAGGCACCCCGCUUCCCCAGCAACAUCAUCGUCACCAACGGCGCGGCCCGGGAGCCCCGCAGGACCCUGUCCAGGGCGGCCGUCAGCGUGCAGGAGCGCAGGGCGCAGGUGUUGGCCACCAUCCACGGCCACGCCGGCGCCUUCCCCGCCGCGGGGGACGCCGGCGAGGGGGCCCCAGGGGGCGGCUCCUCCCCGGAGCGGGUGGCGCGUGGCCGGGGCCUGCCGGGCCCCGCUGAGAGUCUCCGGGCAGGGGGUCAGGCUCCGCGGGGCCCGGCGCUGGCCAACGGCUUCCCAAGUGCGCACGAGGCCCUGAAGAGCGCACCCAGCUCCUUCGCGCCCGCUGGGAAGUCCCUCUGCUUCCGCCCUGGCCCGGCCCUGCCCAGCACGCGGGCCCGUCAGAGCUUCCCCGGGCCCCGGCAGCCCAACGGCGCCCAGGACUGGCGCCGCGCAGACUCCCUGCCCCGGCCCCAGGGCAUCACCGUGCAGUUCGCGGGCCGCGGCUCCUCGGAGGAGGCGCGCAGGGAGGCCCUGCGGAAGCUGGGGCUGCUCAGGGAGAGUUCGUGAGGGCCGCGCGGGCUCCAGUCCACCCCGUUUCUCCCCACCCUGAAGAGAGGGUGAAAGAGUCGCUGCACCCAGGAGCUGUUUGGUCUAAAAUGGAAGUGACAGCGGGAGCCCCUGCCCUCUGUGGCACAUCGGAGUCUAGAGGUGCCUGGCUGGGGCCUCCUGGCUGAGCACGCACCGCAAGCUCCAGCCACCGGCACAGAGAACUCUUCCCUAAAGGAAUCUGGCCGAGGGCUUGUCUCCCUUUUCCCAAGAACUGAGAGAGAGAGAAUAACCUGUUAGACCCAUAGGUUUCCGUGAUGUGUAAAUGCCAUCUUUUGGGGGUUGGGAGGAGUAGGACUGGUCUGAUUAUCAUUCUUGAGUCUCAUCUACCCUCUUCUCGAAGUACAUGACAUGAAAGUUCAGAUCCCUUCCACUCAGGAUUCUCGCCGCCUUUUCUAAGAAAAUAAUAAAAAAAAAUGCUUGUUUCAUUUUUUAAUGUCUUAAUAUACUUGCUUUUGUUUUUGAAGGGUGAGGCAUCAUGGUACUUUGCUUUUGUUUCUUGACGUACUUUAGUUUGCCCAGUUUUGUUUUUUACUGAAAACUGAAAUGAAACCUUUAGAUAUUGAGUUUUGGGAGUGAAAUGGAAAGGUGGUAAUUUUGAGAAAGCAAGUCUCAUCAGACUCUGAGGUCUGGGACGUGUGCGUGAGCCUGUGUUUGUGUGUGUAUGUUUUUAGAUACGUACGUGUCAACACAUACAUGCAUAGGUAUCCUGUGUGUCCACAUGCAUCAUUAUUAUAUAAAUAGAAACUUCUGAACACCCUCCUAAGUCACUACAGGAUGCCAGCGCUUCCUAUUCUUGGGUAGACAGAGCCACCUCAGCAUCCUGAUGGAUGAUACAAGAAAUUGUUACUUCCUAGUAUGGAAGUGUCUUAAGGACACGUCUCCAUGAUAUUUUGGUGAACCAAAAGUGCUUUAUCCUCAACAAAAUGUUCCUCUGUUCCCAGUUAAAGUAAUAUUCCCUGCUUCCAAGUAAGCAAGACUGUUCACUAAAGAAGGAACUUUUUAGAAAACUAAUCUCCUUUAUCAUCCAAUUUUAGUUCUGCAUGUUCCGAGGUAGCCAGUCAACAGAAGGAAGCAAAAGAUUCUUAAAGAUCCACCGACUGUCAUGUUCCACAAGCAAGAUCUCAGGGUAGGGAAAAACCAGUGAAUGAGGUUACACAGCAGGAAAAGAACCGGUUUCCUCCCAGACUAUGUCUUACACGCUGAGUUAUGCCACAAGCGUUAUCAUCAAAACUAUUUAAGGCUGGAGUCUUAGACCUCUAAAAAUAGACAGGAAGGGCUGCCCUGAGCAGUGACACCUUUGUGUUUUUAUGUCUCCGCCAGCGCCGUAACAGAGCCUGUUUCUUUCCCGUUGAGUAUUACUUAAAUUCAGGCUUAAAUGUGCUAUGAAGGGCAUUUUUCAUAGUAUCCCAUUUGCCUUGUAAGUUAUAUAAAGUGCAUGAUUAUAAUUUUUUCCUUAGAAAUGCAAUAUUUAGUUUCAUCCAGCUCUUAUGAAUAAUAACCUCAUAGAUUCCUGAUCUUAAUUUAAAUAGGUGCUUUAAUUUUACAGCUUUCAAAAGUAGUUACUGUAAAUUUUACUCCUGUUAAUGCUGGAUUGGUUUAAAGGAUUUAUAAGGGCUGUGUUUGCUCUUUACAAGGCAAGAUGCCAUACAGUGUUCAAUAAUAGAAGGUCUUGAUACAACCGACAUUUUAAAUAUUCUUUAUACAUGAGGACUGCAUCUUUUUCACUGACCCUAUGAUUUCACUGUGAGUAGGGUGAACUGGACUGCAUAUUAGUUUAUUUGUUGCCAUAAUCACAUUUUUGAAAAAUAAAUUUAAGAGUUUUUUCUUAA